AGUUGGCGCGGGCCGCGGGCGAGGCGGGGCCGCGCGCGGGGUCCCCUCCUCCUGCCGGUCAGGUCCCCUCAGGAGCGCCGGGCGCAGUCUGCGCCUCCCGCUCCCCGCCUCCGGCCGGGUCCGGGACGCCGCGGCUGUGGGGUCGGCCCGCUAAGGACAAGGUCGGGAGACUGGGUGGCGAUGCCCGAGUGCGACUGGAGGCAGCCGAGCGGAGGCGACGGCGGUUGGGAUCUGUCCCUCCUGACCGGGGAGCGGGACUCGGACGGGCGCCGGUGAGGAGGAGGAGAAGCGGCGGCGGAGAGGUUUUCUGCGGCCGGAAUUCCCUUCAACAGCAUCCCUGUCGGCGCCCGCGAGCGCAGUCUCGCCGGGCAGGGGCGCCGGGGAAGAUGGAGACUGGGGGCCGGGCCCGCACUGGUACCCCGCAGCCAGCGGCCCCGGGGGUGUGGAGGGCUCGGCCGGCGGGCGGCGGCGGCGGGGGCGCCUCCUCCUGGCUGCUGGACGGGAACAGCUGGCUGCUGUGCUAUGGCUUCCUCUACCUGGCGCUCUACGCGCAGGUGUCCCAGUCCAAGCCGUGCGAGAGGACCGGCUCCUGCUUCUCGGGCCGCUGUGUCAACUCCACCUGCCUCUGCGACCCGGGCUGGGUGGGGGACCAGUGCCAGCACUGCCAGGGCAGGUUCAAGUUAACAGAACCUUCUGGAUAUUUAACAGAUGGCCCAAUUAACUAUAAAUAUAAAACUAAAUGUACUUGGCUCAUUGAAGGCUAUCCAAAUGCAGUGUUAAGAUUAAGAUUCAAUCAUUUUGCUACAGAAUGUAGCUGGGAUCAUAUGUAUGUUUAUGAUGGAGAUUCAAUAUAUGCACCUUUAAUAGCUGUACUUAGUGGUUUGAUAGUCCCUGAAAUAAGGGGCAAUGAAACUGUGCCUGAAGUUGUUACUACAUCUGGCUAUGCACUGUUACAUUUUUUUAGUGAUGCUGCGUAUAAUCUAACUGGUUUCAACAUUUUCUAUUCAAUCAAUUCUUGUCCUAACAAUUGCUCUGGUCAUGGGAAGUGUACAACUAGUGUCUCUGUUCCAAGUCAAGUAUAUUGUGAAUGUGAUAAAUACUGGAAGGGUGAAGCUUGUGAUAUUCCUUACUGUAAAGCCAAUUGCGGCAGUCCAGAUCACGGUUACUGUGACCUGACUGGAGAAAAAUUAUGUGUCUGCAAUGAUAGUUGGCAAGGUCCUGAUUGUUCUUUGAAUGUUCCCUCUACUGAGUCUUACUGGAUUCUGCCAAACGUUAAACCCUUCAGUCCUUCUGUAGGUCGGGCUUCACAUAAAGCAGUUUUACACGGGAAAUUUAUGUGGGUGAUUGGUGGAUAUACUUUUAACUACAGUUCUUUUCAAAUGGUCCUAAAUUACAAUUUAGAAAGCAGUAUAUGGAAUGUAGGAACUCCAUCAAGGGGACCUCUCCAGAGAUAUGGACACUCUCUUGCUUUAUAUCAGGAAAACAUCUUUAUGUAUGGAGGCAGAAUUGAAACAAAUGAUGGCAAUGUCACAGAUGAAUUAUGGGUUUUUAACAUACAUAGUCAGUCAUGGAGUACAAAAACUCCUACUGUUCUUGGACAUGGUCAGCAGUAUGCUGUGGAGGGACAUUCAGCACAUAUUAUGGAGUUGGAUAGUAGAGAUGUUGUCAUGAUCAUAAUAUUUGGAUAUUCUGCAAUAUAUGGUUAUACAAGCAGCAUACAGGAAUACCAUAUCUCAUCAAACACUUGGCUUGUUCCAGAAACUAAAGGAGCUAUUGUACAAGGUGGAUAUGGCCAUACUAGUGUGUAUGAUGAAAUAACAAAGUCCAUUUAUGUUCAUGGAGGGUAUAAAGCAUUGCCAGGGAACAAAUAUGGAUUGGUUGAUGAUCUUUAUAAAUAUGAAGUUAACACUAAGACUUGGACUAUUUUGAAAGAAAGUGGGUUUGCCAGAUACCUUCAUUCAGCUGUUCUUAUCAAUGGAGCUAUGCUUAUUUUUGGAGGAAAUACCCAUAAUGACACUUCCUUGAGUAACGGUGCAAAAUGUUUUUCUGCCGAUUUCCUGGCAUAUGACAUAGCUUGUGAUGAAUGGAAAAUACUACCAAAACCAAAUCUUCAUAGAGAUGUCAACAGAUUUGGACACUCUGCAGUAGUCAUUAACGGGUCCAUGUAUAUAUUUGGGGGAUUUUCUAGUGUACUCCUUAAUGAUAUCCUUGUAUACAAGCCUCCAAAUUGCAAGGCUUUCAGAGAUGAAGAACUUUGUAAAAAUGCUGGUCCAGGGAUAAAAUGUGUUUGGAAUAAAAAUCACUGUGAAUCUUGGGAAUCUGGGAAUACUAAUAAUAUUCUUAGAGCAAAGUGCCCUCCUAAAACAGCUGCUUCUGAUGACAGAUGUUACAGAUAUGCAGAUUGUGCCAGCUGUACUGCCAAUACAAAUGGGUGCCAAUGGUGUGAUGACAAGAAAUGCAUUUCGGCAAAUAGUAACUGCAGUAUGUCUGUCAAGAACUACACCAAAUGUCAUGUGAGAAAUGAGCAGAUUUGUAACAAACUUACCAGCUGUAAAAGCUGUUCACUAAACUUGAAUUGCCAGUGGGAUCAGAGACAGCAAGAAUGCCAGGCUUUACCAGCUCAUCUUUGUGGAGAAGGAUGGAGUCAUAUUGGGGAUGCUUGUCUUAGAGUCAAUUCCAGUAGAGAAAACUAUGACAAUGCAAAACUUUAUUGCUAUAAUCUUAGUGGAAAUCUUGCUUCAUUAACAACCUCAAAAGAAGUAGAAUUUGUUCUGGAUGAAAUACAGAAGUAUACACAACAGAAAGUAUCACCUUGGGUAGGCUUGCGCAAGAUCAAUAUAUCCUAUUGGGGAUGGGAAGACAUGUCUCCUUUUACAAACACAACACUACAGUGGCUUCCUGGCGAACCCAAUGAUUCUGGGUUUUGUGCAUAUCUGGAAAGGGCUGCAGUGGCAGGCUUAAAAGCUAAUCCUUGUACAUCUAUGGCAAAUGGCCUUGUCUGUGAAAAACCUGUUGUUAGUCCAAAUCAAAAUGCGAGGCCGUGCAAAAAGCCAUGCUCUCUGAGGACAUCAUGUUCCAACUGUACAAGCAAUGGCAUGGAGUGUAUGUGGUGCAGCAGUACGAAACGAUGUGUUGACUCUAAUGCCUAUAUCAUCUCUUUUCCAUAUGGACAAUGUCUAGAGUGGCAAACUGCCACCUGCUCCCCUCAAAAUUGUUCUGGAUUGAGAACCUGUGGACAGUGUUUGGAACAGCCUGGAUGUGGCUGGUGCAAUGAUCCUAGUAAUACAGGAAGAGGACAUUGCAUUGAAGGUUCUUCACGGGGACCAAUGAAGCUUAUUGGAAUGCACCACAGUGAGAUGGUUCUUGACACCAAUCUUUGCCCCAAAGAAAAGAACUAUGAGUGGUCCUUUAUCCAGUGUCCAGCUUGCCAGUGUAAUGGACAUAGCACUUGCAUCAAUAAUAAUGUGUGCGAACAGUGUAAAAAUCUCACCACAGGAAAGCAGUGUCAAGAUUGUAUGCCAGGUUAUUAUGGAGAUCCAACCAAUGGUGGACAGUGCACAGCUUGUACAUGCAGUGGCCAUGCAAAUAUCUGUCAUCUGCACACAGGAAAAUGUUUCUGCACAACUAAAGGAAUAAAAGGUGACCAAUGCCAAUUAUGUGACUCUGAAAAUCGCUAUGUUGGUAAUCCACUUAGAGGAACAUGUUAUUACAGCCUUUUGAUUGAUUAUCAAUUUACCUUCAGCUUAUUACAGGAAGAUGAUCGCCACCAUACUGCCAUAAACUUUAUAGCAAACCCAGAACAGUCGAACAAAAAUCUGGAUAUAUCAAUUAAUGCAUCAAACAACUUUAAUCUCAACAUUACGUGGUCUGUCGGUUCAACAGCUGGAACAAUAUCUGGGGAAGAGACUUCUAUAGUUUCCAAGAAUAAUAUAAAGGAAUACAGAGAUAGUUUUUCCUAUGAAAAAUUUAACUUUAGAAGCAAUCCUAACAUUACAUUCUAUGUGUACGUCAGCAACUUUUCCUGGCCUAUUAAAAUACAGAUUGCAUUCUCACAACACAAUACAAUCAUGGACCUUGUGCAGUUUUUUGUCACCUUCUUCAGUUGUUUCCUAUCCUUAUUGCUGGUGGCUGCUGUGGUAUGGAAGAUCAAACAAACUUGUUGGGCUUCUCGACGGAGAGAGCAACUGCUUCGAGAACGACAGCAGAUGGCCAGCCGUCCCUUUGCUUCUGUUGAUGUAGCUCUGGAAGUGGGAGCUGAACAAACAGAGUUUCUGCGAGGGCCAUUAGAGGGGGCACCCAAGCCAAUUGCCAUUGAACCAUGUGCUGGGAACAGAGCUGCUGUUCUGACUGUGUUUCUUUGUCUACCACGAGGAUCAUCAGGUGCCCCUCCCCCUGGGCAGUCAGCUAACUGCCGAUCCUGUGGGUCUUCAGCCAACACCUCUCACCUGCUGAGCAGCAGCAUCUCAACCUGGAUUUCCUCCCGUUCAGAUGUAAAGUGAGCCGUCCUUCCCCCUUUCCUCUGUCACUUCCCACCAUUCCCCAGACCAGCUCUUCUCUCCUGACUUGUCUGUUUUUGUAAAGUCUGUUUCAGAAUGGCUCAAGUUUGAAACCUUCAAAUUAGCCUGUCUUCUCUCUCUUUGUGCCCUUUUACAUCUCAGUAAUCGUGAAGUUCUAUAGAUUUUAUCCCUGGAGCGGACAGAGAAGACAUCUUAUUUUUUCCAUUCUUAUUCCCUCCAUGCUUUGUUCUGGGAGUGGUUGCUUCUCACCUGGGUUGCUCCCAAAGGAAGGCACAGCUCUAAUCAUAUCGCUUCCUCAUACCUUUGCAGACUUUUCAUUGCCUGUUGAAAUAGGUCCAGACGUUUACUCUGGAAUGAAAGGUCCUCUCUGACUUCUCCUCAACUUCUCUUCCAGGUUUAGCACCCUCAGAGUCCUAAGCCUACCUGCACAGCACCACUGGCUACAUGGGGGUCCUUGGACAAUUAUUUUAAACUCUCAGACCUUUAGUUUCUUCAUGUAUAACAUUAGAAAAAUGACUAGAUAAAAUAUCUUUGUGAUUGCUGCUAGGCCUAUCAUUCCAUACAUAUUUUUCUUAUGAUUCUCUGAGUGUAGGUGUGGUCUGUCAUACUGCUGUUUCUUGUACCCGAAAUCCCCUGUGUUAGGCUGCUUAUUUUCAAAGCCUGGUUCAAAUGCUAUUUCGUCUUCCUUGAGACCUUUUCAGUCCCUUCCAUACAAAUGUGACCUCACUGUCUUGAAAUCCCACACCUUCUAACAUAUAUCCAUGCCUUCUAACAUAUAUCAGAGUUGCUAUGUUCUUUUCUUUUUUCCCCAGUAGUAAGCUCUCUGAAGGCAGUGGCAAUAUCUUAUUUCAUCUUUGAAUCCCUAGCUGCUAACAAGUUUCUGGUACUUAAUAGUUGCUUGAUAAAUAUUUAAUUGAUGAAUAAAAUUAUCUUUAAAUUUUGGAGACUCUUCACCAAAAAAGAUGUGCAAAAGAUGUAUACUCCACAAAUGUAUACUUUACGAUGUAAAGUUUCACUUCAAGCCCAUAACCUCGAUAGACUGGAUUUUGUGUUUUUAUAAUUCAUGUAGGAUGGAUCAAGCUACAUAUCUCAGGGACCGAAAUCAAGCCCAAAACUGUACUUUCAAUGGAUUACAUCUAUGAAAACUAACUUGUUUAGCUUUAAGUUUCAAUGAACAUGAGAAUAUUAGUGAAAGAUGACACAAAACAAUAAAGCAAUUUAUAUUUCCAAUGUAGCAUGUCUGAAACCUAUCAUAGAGAUCUUCUGUUUUCAUGAUUUGAACACUGAUUUAUUCCUUGGAUAGUAAUUUUUUUAACUAUUUUAUUUAAGUUUGAAAGAGCCCAACUCAAUUCUACCCUUUAUGACCAGAAAAAUAAAUUACUUUGAAUCUUAUGGAAAUGUCCACAUAUUAGUUAUACUCAGGACAGAUAACCUCACAAAAGAUAACUGGCAAAUAAAAAGCAUCAAUUGUUGGUGUAGUCAUUAAAACAUACUGUUUGGAAGACCAGGCACGGUAGCUCAUGCCUGUAAUCCCAGCACUUUGGGAGGCCGAGGCAGGUGGAUCACCUGAGGUCAGAAUUCAGGACUAGCCUGGCCAACAUAGUGAAAUCCCGUCUCUACUAAAAAUACAAAAAUUAGCCAGGCGUGGUGGCAGAUGCCCGUAAUCCCAGCUACUGGGGAGGCUGAGGCAGGAGAAACGCUUGAACCCAGCAGGCAGAGGUUGCAGUAAACCGAGAUCGUGCCAUUGCACUCCAGCCUGGGCAACAAGAGCGAAGCUCCAUCUCAAAAAAAAAAAAAAAAAAAAAAGCCAUACAUACUGUUCGUUGUGAAUCUAUUCUUUGCACCAUGCUGUCCUUUGAGUUACUGUAACCCUAUAGGGCAGCAGUCCCCAACCUUUUGGCACCAGGGACGGGUUUCGUGGAAGACAAUUUUCCACAGACCUGGGGGUCAGUGGCAGGGGUGAUGGUUUUGGGAUUAAACUGUUGCACUACAGGUCAUCAGGCAUUAGUUACAUUCUCACAAAGAGUUUGCAGCCUAGAUCCCUCACAUGCGCAGUUCACAAUAGGGUUCGUGCUCCUUUGAGAAUCUAAUGCCUCCGCUGAUCCGACAGGAGGCGGAGCUCAGGCUGUGAUGUUCACUCACACCCACCCAUUGCACAACUUCUGCUGUGAGUGCUGUGAGGCCCGGUUCUCAAUAGGCUACAGGCUGGUACAUGUAUGCAGCCUGGGGUUGGGAGCCCUUGCUGUGAGGUAUAUGCAGUUGACCCUUGAACAACAUGGGUUUGAACUGUGUGGGCUCAUUUAUAUGCAGAUUUUCUUCUGUCUCUGCCACCCUGAGACACCAAGACCAGCCUCUCCUUUUCCUUCUCCUCCUCCUUCUCUGCUUACUCAAAAAUGAAGACAAUUAGGAUAAAAAUCUUUAUAAUGAUCUAUUUCCACUUAAUGAAUAGUAAAUAUAUUUUCUCUUCUUUAUGAUUUUCUUAAUAACAUUUUCCUUUUUCUAGCUUACUUUAUUGUAAUAAUACAAUAUAUAACAUAUACAACAUACAAAAUACGUGUUAAUCAACUGUUUAGAUUAUUGGCAAGGCUUCUGAUAAAAAAUAGGCUAUUAGUAGUUAAGUUCUGGAGGAGUGAAAAGUUAUACAGGGACUUUAAACUGCACAGGGGGUUGGCACUCCAACCCCCAUUUUAUUCAAAGGUCAACUGUGUUAUCACUUUUCUUUUAUAUAUGAGAAAAAUGAACCAUGGAUAUUAAGUAACUUGCCUACAGUCACAUAGUAAAUAAUUAUGGAGUCAGAAUUUAAAACCAGAAAACUUUUACAUCAAAAUGCUCUUUAUAAAUGUUUUUGUUUUGUUUUGUUUUUUCAUUUCUUAGCUAUGAGUAAAGACCAUUAGCUGUUUGUGUUUUGAGGACAGCACAAGCUUUUUCUUUUACUGACCAGUGUCACUGUAAAAUGACAUGGUGAUGGUCCUUCCAUUUCAGACUUUUAAAUAUAUCUUUCCGUCACUUUUGUGAGAAAUUGAUUAAUAUGUAAAGGAAACAAAAGAAAAUAAGGAUGAGAAGCUUAAAGAAUAGUGAAAAUGGCUAAUUAAACAUGCUGCAGAAAAGAGUCAACUUUAAAAGUUAAUUCAAAUACUUUAAAGACUGACCAAUUAGAAACAAACUCACAUGACAAAUCAGGAUUCAUGGAAAUGAAAAAUGAGACCACUAGCACUGAAACGUGACCAACACAUUUUUCUUUUCUUUUUUCUUCUUUCCCACCUGCCACCUCUUUCUGGUAUUUCUGGAAUUCACUGUUAAUAAUUACUGUGCUCAAAGAGAAAAACAGGAAAAAAUUAAAACUCAACAAGACAACUUACAAAACCAAAGAGGAAAAUCAAAAUGUGUUGCAAUACCCAAGCUGCCUUUGAAGCAACAAAACAACAAAGCAAGAAUGUUGUGGGUGUGAAUACAAUGUUAUGGGUCAACUAUUGUGAAAGACAGUAUGGUAAUUCCUCAAAGAUUUAGAACUGGAAAUACCAUUUAACCCAGCAAUCCCAUUGCUGAGUGUUUACGCAAAGGAAUAUAAAUAAUUCUAUUAUAAAGAUACAUGCACGCAUAUGUUCAUUGCAGCACUGUUCACAAUAGCAAAGACAAAGACCAAAAUGCCCAUCAAUGAUAGCCUGGAUAAAGAAAAUGUGGUGGUAUAUAUACACCAUGGAGUACUAUACAGCCAUAAAAAGGAAUGAGAUCAUGUCCUUUGCAGGGACAUGGAUGAAGCUGAAAGCCAUUAUCCUGAGCAAACUAACACAGGAAGAGAAAGCCAAAUACUGCAUGUUCUUAUUUCUAACUGGGAGCUGAACAAUGAGAACACAUGGAAAUAGUGAGGGGAACAACAUACACUGGAGCCUGUCGGGGGAGAGAGGGGUUGUGGAGAGAGCAUUAGGAAAAAUAGCUAAUGCAUGCUGGGCUUAAAACCUAGGUGAUGGGUUGAUAGGUUCAGCAAACCACCAUGGCACACGUUUACCUAUGUAACAAACCUGCACAUCUGCACAUGGACCUCGGAACUUAAAAUAAAAUAAAUGUUAAGGGUAAGUUUGUGAGGUCCUCCAUUUUUUUUUAUGAUAGCUGACACCAUGGUUUAUAUAAAACUGCCAAUUGGUAAAAAAAAUUACUUUUAAUUGGUUAUGAAUUAAAUAGUCCUACUUUACAUAGGUUUGGGAGAAUUUAACAGAAGUUUGCUGCCUUCAUUACCUCGGGCUGCUAUAAUAAAAUAUUAGAGUCUCGGUGACUUAAACAACAAACAUUUGUUUCUCACAGUUCUGGAGGCUGGGAAGUCCAAGAUCAAGAUGCCUGGACAAUUUGGUGUCUGGUAAGGGCCCUUUUCCUGGUUUGCAGAUGAUCACCUAUAGCUGUAUCCUCACAUGGCAGAGAAAAAGAGCUCUGAUUUCUUCUUAUAAGGGCACUAAUCUCAUCCUGAAGCUCCACUCUCUUGCCCUUAUCUAAACCUAAUUAGUCCUCCCCAAAAACCCCCCACCUCCAAAUACCAUUAUAUUAGGGAUUAGUGCUUCAAUGUAUGAAUUUGGUAGAAGGUGGGGCACAAACAUUCAGGCCAUAGCAGGCUUCUUCUGUAGUUAAAAAGAAUGGAAGGGUUCUGAGUCUCAGAAUGACUAGAACCAAGGUGUCUGGAUCUCUCAAGCAGGGAGCGAGAGAUCCAGAGACCUUGGUUGUAGUCCCUGCUCAUAUUACCCCUCCCUCAUAUUUAUUGUAACAUGUUGCAAAACCUAACCAGAAAAAGAAAAUAAUAUAAUUCACCUCUUACCAGCAGGCAGUACUGCACAAUUCUGCCACACAGAGCCCAGAAAAGGCAGGCAGAAGGGAACUCCCUAGAUCCAGAAAGGAAAAUUAAGUGACUUGAGAAAAUAUGUAAAGGCUAAGACUGGGUAAGUGGCCCUGCAAAUUCCUUCUAGUCACAGAAACAUUUUUCUGGGGGUCACCUCAUAGGGCCAGUGGUCCGUCAGCAAAUCCAGAAGUAUGUUCAAGUUUUGAUCAAAACUCCAUGUUAUACUGAUAGCUGGUUUAAUCUCGGGUCCUCCCACAGACUGUUUAAUGGUGCCAUAGUAUCUACCAAAGGCAUUUUUGAGUAUGGAUGUCCCCUUACUCUUAAUGGAAGUCCUGGUGGAGGAGCAAGUGCCAGCAGUAAAAAUGUAAUUCUAUAAAAGGUAAAUGUUGAUUACAAUUAUAUUAACUCCUUAAGACCACAGUGAUCUUUCUCUAAGAGCUUGUAGGGAAAAAGUUAAUGGCCCUCUGAAAAGAGAGUAAUUCAUUUCCUUUUAUCCACUUUAUAAUUUGCAAAUUUGCAAAUGAGCAUAGCCCAUGCAAGUUGAGCAGGCUUCUCUCACUGAUGGGUAGCAUAUCCAAAGCUUUCAUGCAGGUAAAAGCACUGGAAAAAAUAUGAGAGAGUUCAUCUUCUUCCUUAGGAGCUGGGACUGAAACUGGUCCACAGGACUUCAGGGAGGUGGUUUGAGGAAUCCUACAUGGUCCCUGGGAUCAUCAUUUAGAAGCUUUGAGGGAAUAAAGAUUCUUGUUCUCUGAA